CUCUUUUGUCCUCUUCCCAGGUUCCCUGGCCCCUUCGGAGAAACGCACUUGGUUCGGGCCAGCCGCCUGAGGGGACGGGCUCACGUCUGCUCCUCACACUGCAGCUGCUGGGCCGUGGAGCUUCCCCAGGGAGCCAGGGGGACUUUUGCCGCAGCCAUGAAGGGGGCACGCUGGAGGAGGGUCCCCUGGGUGUCCCUGAGCUGCCUGUGUCUCUGCCUCCUUCCGCAUGUGGUCCCAGGAACCACAGAGGACACAUUAAUAACUGGAAGUAAAACUCCUGCCCCAGUCACCUCAACAGGCUCAACAACAGCGACACUAGAGGGACAAUCAACUGCAGCUUCUUCAAGGACCUCUAAUCAGGACAUAUCAGCUUCAUCUCAGAACCACCAGACUAAGAGCACGGAGACCACCAGCAAAGCUCAAACCGACACCCUCACGCAGAUGAUGACAUCAACUCUUUUUUCUUCCCCAAGUGUACACAAUGUGAUGGAGACUGUUACGCAGGAGACAGCUCCUCCAGAUGAAAUGACCACAUCAUUUCCCUCCAGUGUCACCAACACACUCAUGAUGACAUCAAAGACUAUAACAAUGACAACCUCCACAGACUCCACUCUUGGAAACACAGAAGAGACAUCAACAGCAGGAACUGAAAGUUCUACCCCAGUGACCUCAGCAGUCUCAAUAACAGCUGGACAGGAAGGACAAUCACGAACAACUUCCUGGAGGACCUCUAUCCAAGACACAUCAGCUUCUUCUCAGAACCACUGGACUCGGAGCACGCAGACCACCAGGGAAUCUCAAACCAGCACCCUAACACACAGAACCACUUCAACUCCUUCUUUCUCUCCAAGUGUACACAAUGUGACAGGGACUGUUUCUCAGAAGACAUCUCCUUCAGGUGAAACAGCUACCUCAUCCCUCUGUAGUGUCACAAACACAUCCAUGAUGACAUCAGAGAAGAUAACAGUGACAACCUCCACAGGCUCCACUCUUGGAAACCCAGGGGAGACAUCAUCAGUACCUGUUACUGGAAGUCUUAUGCCAGUCACCUCAGCAGCCUUAGUAACAGUUGAUCCAGAAGGACAAUCACCAGUAACUUUCUCAAGGACUUCUACUCAGGACACAACAGCUUUUUCUAAGAACCACCAGACUCAGAGCGUGGAGACCACCAGAGUAUCUCAAAUCAACACCCUCAACACCCUCACACCGGUUACAACAUCAACUGUUUUAUCCUCACCAAGUGGAUUCAACCCAAGUGGAACAGUUUCUCAGGAGACAUUCCCUUCUGGUGAAACAACCAUCUCAUCCCCUUCCAGUGUCAGCAAUACAUUCCUGGUAACAUCAAAGGUGUUCAGAAUGCCAAUCUCCAGAGACUCUACUCUUGGAAACACAGAGGAGACAUCACUAUCUGUAAGUGGAACCAUUUCUGCAAUCACUUCCAAAGUUUCAACCAUAUGGUGGUCAGACACUCUGUCAACAGCACUCUCCCCCAGUUCUCUACCUCCAAAAAUAUCCACAGCUUUCCACACCCAGCAGAGUGAAGGUGCAGAGACCACAGGACGGCCUCAUGAGAGGAGCUCAUUCUCUCCAGGUGUGUCUCAAGAAAUAUUUACUCUACAUGAAACAACAACAUGGCCUUCCUCAUUCUCCAGCAAAGGCCACACAACUUGGUCACAAACAGAACUGCCCUCAACAUCAACAGGUGCUGCCACUAGGCUUGUCACAGGAAAUCCAUCUACAGGGGCAGCUGGCACUAUUCCAAGGGUCCCCUCUAAGGUCUCAGCAAUAGGGGAACCAGGAGAGCCCACCACAUACUCCUCCCACAGCACAACUCUCCCAAAAACAACAGGGGCAGGCGCCCAGACACAAUGGACACAAGAAACGGGGACCACUGGAGAGGCUCUUCUCAGCAGCCCAAGCUACAGUGUGACUCAGAUGAUAAAAACGGCCACAUCCCCAUCUUCUUCACCUAUGCUGGAUAGACACACAUCACAACAAAUUACAACGGCACCAUCAACAAAUCAUUCAACAAUACAUUCCACAAGCACCUCUCCUCAGGAAUCACCAGCUGUUUCCCAAAGGGGUCACACUCAAGCCCCGCAGACCACACAAGAAUCACAAACCACGAGGUCCGUCUCCCCCAUGACUGACACCAAGACAGUCACCACCCCAGGUUCUUCCUUCACAGCCAGUGGGCACUCGCCCUCAGAAAUUGUUCCUCAGGACGCACCCACCAUAAGUGCAGCAACAACCUUUGCCCCAGCUCCCACCGGGGAUGGUCACACAACCCAGGCCCCGACCACAGCACUGCAGGCAGCACCCAGCAGCCAUGAUGCCACCCUGGGGCCCUCAGGAGGCACGUCACUUUCCAAAACAGGUGCCCUUACUCUGGCCAACUCUGUAGUGUCAACACCAGGGGGCCCAGAAGGACAAUGGACAUCAGCCUCUGCCAGCACCUCACCUGACACAGCAGCAGCCAUGACCCAUACCCACCAGGCUGAGAGCACAGAGGCCUCUGGACAAACACAGACCAGCGAACCGGCCUCCUCAGGGUCACGAACCACCUCAGCGGGCACAGCUACCCCUUCCUCAUCCGGGGCGAGUGGCACAACACCUUCAGGAAGCGAAGGAAUAUCCACCUCAGGAGAGACGACAAGGUUUUCAUCAAACCCCUCCAGGGACAGUCACACAACCCAGUCAACAACCGAAUUGCUGUCCGCCUCAGCCAGUCAUGGUGCCAUCCCAGUAAGCACAGGAAUGGCGUCUUCGAUCGUCCCCGGCACCUUUCAUCCCACCCUCUCUGAGGCCUCCACUGCAGGGAGACCGACAGGACAGUCAAGCCCAACUUCUCCCAGUGCCUCUCCUCAGGAGACAGCCGCCAUUUCCCGGAUGGCCCAGACUCAGAGGACAAGAACCAGCAGAGGGUCUGACACUAUCAGCCUGGCGUCCCAGGCAACCGACACCUUCUCAACAGUCCCACCCACACCUCCAUCGAUCACAUCCAGUGGGCUUACAUCUCCACAAACCCAGACCCACACUCUGUCACCUUCAGGGUCUGGUAAAACCUUCACCACGGCCCUCAUCAGCAACGCCACCCCUCUUCCUGUCACCUACGCUUCCUCGGCAUCCACAGGUCACACCACCCCUCUUCAUGUCACCGAUGCUUCCUCAGUAUCCACAGGUCACGCCACCCCUCUUCCUGUCACCGACACUUCCUCAGAAUCCACAGGUCACGCCACCCCUCUUCCUGUCACCAGCCCUUCCUCAGUAUCCACAGGUCACACCACCCCUCUUCCUGUCACCGACACUUCCUCAGAAUCCACAGGUCAUGUCACCCCUCUUCCUGUCACCAGCCUUUCCUCAGCAUCCACAGGUGACAGCACCCCUCUUCCUGUCACUGACACUUCCUCAGCAUCCACAGGUCACGUCACCCCUCUUCCUGUCACCAGCCUUUCCUCAGCAUCCACAGGUGACACCACCCCUCUUCCUGUCACUGACACUUCCUCAGCAUCCACAGGUCACGCCACCUCUCUUCCUGUCACCGACACUUCCUCAGUAUCCACAGGUCACACCACCCCUCUUCCUGUCACCGACACUUCCUCAGCAUCCACAGGUCACGCCACCUCUCUUCCUGUCACCGACACUUCCUCAGUAUCCACAGCUCACGCCACCCCACUUCCUGUCACCGGCCUUUCUUCAGCUUCCACAGAUGACACCACCCGUCUUCCUGUCACCGACGUUUCCUCGGCAUCCACAGGUCAGGCCAUCCCUCUUCCUGUCACCAGCCCUUCCUCAGCAUCCACAGGUGACACCACCCCUCUUCCUGUCACCGACGCUUCCUCAGCAUCCACAGGUGACACCACCUCUCUUCCUGUCACCAUCCCUUCCUCAGCAUCUUCAGGUCACACCACCUCUCUUCCUGUCACCGACGCUUCCUCAGUGUCCACAGGUCACGCCACCUCUCUUCUUGUCACCGACGCUUCCUCAGUAUCCACAGGUGACACCACCCCUCUUCCUGUCACCGACACUAACUCAGCAUCCACAGGUGACACCACCCCUCUUCAUGUCACCGACGCUUCCUCAGUAUCCACAGGUCACGCCACCUCUCUUCCUGUCACCAGCCUUUCCUCAGCAUCCACAGGUGACACCACGCCUCUUCCUGUCACUAGCCCUUCCUCAGCAUCCUCAGGUCACACCACCCCUCUUCCUGUCACCGACGCUUCCUCAGUACCCACAGGUCACGCCACCUCUCUUCCUGUCACCGACGCUUCCUCAGUGUCCACAGGUCACGCCACCCCUCUUCCUGUCACCGACGCUUCCUCAGUGUCCACAGGUCAUGCCACCCCUCUUCCGGUCACCGACACUUCCUCAGUAUCUACAGGACAGGCCACCCCUCUUCCUGUCACCAGCCUUUCCUCAGCAUCCACUGGUGACACCACGCCGCUUCCUGUCACCGAUACUUCCUCAGCAUCCACAGGUCAGGACACCCCUCUUCCUGUCACCAGCCUUUCCUCAGUAUCCACAGGUGACACCACGCCUCUUCCUGUCACUAGCCCUUCCUCAGCAUCCACAGGUCACGCCACCCCUCUUCUUGUCACCGACGCUUCCUCAGUAUCCACAGGUCACGCCACCUCUCUUCUUGUCACCGACGCUUCCUCAGUAUCCACAGGUCACGCCACCGCUCUUCAUGUCACCGAUGCUUCCUCAUUAUCCACAGGGGACACCACCCCUCUUCCUGUCACCAGCCCUUCCUCAGCAUCCACAGGUGACACCACCCCUCUUCCUGUCACCGACACUUCCUCAGCAUCCACAGGUCACGCCACCUCUCUUCCUGUCACCGACACUUCCUCAGCAUCCACAGGUCACGCCACCCCUCUUCCUGUCACCGACACUUCCUCAGCAUCCACAGGUCAGGCCACCCCUCUUCCUGUCACCGGCCCUUCCUCAGCAUCCACAGGUCACGCCAUCCCUCUUCUUGUCACCGACACUUCCUCAGCAUCCACAGGACAGGCCACCCCUCUUCCUGUCACCAGCCUUUCCUCAGCAUCCACAGGUGACACCACCCCUCUUCCUGUCACCGACGCUUCCUCAGUGUCCACAGGUCACGCCACCUCUCUUCCUGUCACCAGCCUUUCCUCAGUAUCCACAGGUGACACCACCCCUCUUCCUGUCACCAGCCCUUCCUCAGCAUCCUCAGGUCACACCACCCCUCUUCCUGUCACCGACGCUUCCUCAGUAUCCACAGGUGACACCACCCCUCUUCCUGUCACCAGCCCUUCCUCAGCAUCCUCAGGUCACACCACCCCUCUUCCUGUCACCAGCCCUUCCUCAGCAUCCUCAGGUCACACCACCCCUCUUCCUGUCACCGACGCUUCCUCAGCAUCCACAGGUGACACCACCCCUCUUCCUGUCACCGACACUUCCUCAGCAUCCACAGGUCACGCCACCCAUCUUCCUGUCACCGGCCUUUCCUCAGCUUCCACAGGUGACACCACCCGUCUUCCUGUCACCAACGUUUCCUCGGCAUCCACAGGUCAUGCCACCCCUCUUCCUGUCACCAGCACUUCCUCAGCAUCCACAGGUGACACCACCCCUCUUCCUGGCACCGACACUUCCUCAGUAUCCACAGGUCACACCACCCCUCUUCUUGUCACCGACGCUUCGUCAGUAUCCACAGGUGACACCACCCGUCUUCCUGUCACCAGCCCUUCCUCAGCAUCUACAGGUCACACCACCCCUCUACCUGUCACCGACACUCCCUCAGCAUCCACAGGUGACACCACCCCUCUUCCUGUCACCAAUGCUUCCUCAUUAUCCACACGUCACACCACCUCUCUUCAUGUCACCAGCCCUUCCUCAGCAUCCACAGGUCACGCCACCUCUCUUCCUGUCACCGACACUUCCUCAGUAUCCACAGGUCAUGCCACCCCUCUUCAUGUCACCAGCCCUUCCUCAGCAUCCACAGGUGACACCACCCCUCUUCCUGUCACCGACACUUACUCAGCAUCCACAGGUCAGGCCACCCCUCUUCCUGUCACCGACACUUCCUCAGCAUCCACAGGUGACACCACCCCUCUUCCUGUCACCGACACUUCCUCAGCAUCCACAGGUCACGCCACCCCUCUUCCUGUCACCAACACUUCCUCAGUAUCCACAGGUCACGCCACCCCUCUUCAUGUCACCAGCCCUUCCUCAGCAUCCACAGGUCACACCACCCCUCUUCCUGUCACCGACGCUUCGUCAGUGUCCACAGGUCACGCCACCUCUCUUCCUGUCACCGACGCUUCCUCAGUGUUCACAGGUCACGCCACCUCGCUUCCUGUCACCAUCCCUUCCUCAGCAUCCUCAGGUCACACCACCCCUCUUCCUGUCACCGACGCUUCCUCAGUGUCCACAGGUCACGCCACCUCUCUUCCUGUCACCGACGCUUCCUCAGUGUCCACAGGUCACGCCACCCCUCUUCCUGUCACCGACGCUUCCUCAGUGUCCACAGGUCACGCUACCCCUCUUCCUGUCACCGACACUUCCUCAGUAUCCACAGGUCACGCCACCCCUCUUCCUCUCACCAGCCUUUCCUCAGUAUCCACAGGUGACACCACGCCUCUUCCUGUCACCGACACUUCCUCAGCAUCCACAGGUCAGGCCACCCCUCUUCCUGUCACCAGCCUUUCCUCAGUAUCCACAGGUGACACCACCCCUCUUCCUGUCACCGACACUUCCUCAGCAUCCACAGGUCACGCCACCUCUCUUCCUGUCACCGACACUUCCUCAGCAUCCACAGGUCACGCCACCCCUCUUCCUGACACCGACACUUCCUCAGCAUCCACAGGUCACGCCACCCCUCUUCCUGUCACCGACACUUCCUCAGCAUCCACAGGUCACGCCACCCUUCUUCCUGUCACCGACACUUCCUCAGCAUCCAUAGGUCACGCCACCCCUCUUCCUGUCACCGACACUUCCUCAAUAUCCACAGGUCACGCCACCCCUCUUCAUGUCACCAGCCCUUCCUCAGCAUCCACCGGUCACGCCACCCCGCUUCCUGUCACCGACACUUCCUCAGCAUCCACAGGUCACGCCAACCCUCUUCAUGUCACCAGCCCUUCCUCAGCAUCCACCGGUCACGCCACCCCGCUUCCUGUCACCGACACUUCCUCAGCAUCCACAGGUCACGCCACCCCUCUUCCUGUCACCAGCCUUUCCUCAGUAUCCACAGGUGACACCACGCCUCUUCCUGUCACUAGCCCUUCCUCAGCAUCCACAGGUCACACCACCCCUCUUCCUGUCACCGACACUUCCUCAGCAUCCACAGGUCAGGCCACCGCUCUUCCUGUCACCAGCACUUCCUCAGCAUCCACAGGUGACACCACCCCUCUUCCUGUUACCGACACUUCCUCAGCAUCCACAGGUCAGGCCACCCCUCUUCCUGUCACCAGCCUUUCCUCAGUAUCCACAGGUGACACCACGCCUCUUCCUGUCACUAGCCCUUCCUCAGCAUCCACAGGUCACGCCACUCCUCUUCUUGUCACCGACGCUUCCUCAGCAUCCACAGGUCAGGCCACCCCUCUUCCUGUCACCGACACUUCCUCAGCAUACACAGGUGACACCACCUCUCUUCCUGUCACCGACACUUCCUCAUCAUCCACAGGUGACACCACCCCUCUUCUUGUCACCGAGACUUCCUCAGCAUCCACAGGUCACGCCACCCCUCUUCAUGUCACCAGCCCUUCCUCAGCAUCCACAGGUGACACCACCCCUGUGCCUGUCACCGACACUUCCUCAGUAUCCACAGGUCACGCCACCCCUCUUCCUGUCACCGGCCUUUCCUCAGCUUCCACAGGUGACACCACCCGUCUUCCUGUCACCGACAUUUCCUCGGCAUCCACAGGUCAGGCCACCCCUCUUCCUGUCACCAACACUUCCUCAGCAUCCACAGGUCACGCCACCCCUCUUCCUGUCACCGGCCUUUCCUCAGCUUCCACAGGUGACACCACCCGUCUUCCUGUCACCGACAUUUCCUCGGCAUCCACAGGUCAGGCCACCCCUCUUCCUGUCACCAACACUUCCUCAGUAUCCACAGGUGACACCAUGCCUCUUCCUGUCACUAGCCCUUCCUCAGCAUCCACAGGUCACGCCACCCCUCUUCCUGUCACCAGCACUUCCUCAGCAUCCACCGGUCACGCCACCCCUGUUCCUGUCACCAGCACUUCCUCAGCAUCUACAGGUCACACCACCCCUCUUCCUGUCACCGACACUUCCUCAGCAUCCACAGGUGACACCACCCCUCUUCCUGUCACCAGCCCUUCCUCAGCAUCUACAGGUCACACCACCCCUCUUCAUGUCACCAUCCCUUCCUCAGCAUCCACAGGUGACACCAGCACUCUUCCUGUCACCGGCGCUUCCUCAGCAUCCACCGGUCACGCCACCCCUCUUCCUGUCACCGACACUUCCUCAGUAUCCACAGGUCACGCCACCCCUCUUCCUGUCACCAGCUUUUCCUCAGUAUCCACAGGUGACACCACGCCUCUUCCUGUCACCGACACUUCCUCAGUAUCCACAGGUCACGCCACCCCUCUUCCUGUCACCAGCUUUUCCUCAGUAUCCACAGGUGACACCACCCCUCUUCCUGUCACCGACGCUUCCUCGGCAUCCACCGGUCACGCCACCCCUCUUCCUGUCACCGACACUUCCUCAGUAUCCACAGGUCACGCCACCCCUCUUCCUCUCACCAGCCUUUCCUCAGUAUCCACAGGUGACACCACGACUCUUCCUGUCACCGACACUUCCUCAGUAUCCACAGGUCACGCCACCCCUCUUCCUGUCACCAGCUUUUCCUCAGUAUCCACAGGUGACACCACCCCUCUUCCUGUCACCGACGCUUCCUCGGCAUCCACCGGUCACGCCACCCCUCUUCCUGUCACCGACACUUCCUCAGUAUCCACCGGUCACGCCACGCCUCUUCCUGUCACCAGCCUUUCCUCAGUAUCCACAGGUGACACCACCCCUCUUCCUGUCACCGACGCUUCCUCGGCAUCCACAGGUCAGGCCACCCCUCUUCCUGUCACCAGCCUUUCCUCAGUAUCAACAGGUGACACCACGCCUCUUCCUGUCACCAUCCCUUCCUCAGCAUCCUCAGGUCACACCACCUCUCUUCCUGUCACCGACACUUCCUCAGCAUCCACAGGUCAGGCCACCCCUCUUCCUGUCACCAGCCUUUCCUCAGUAUCCACAGGUGACACCACCCCUCUUCUUGUCACCGACGCUUCCUCAGUAUCCACAGGUCACGCCACCCCUCUUCCUGUCACCGACACUUCCUCAGCAUCCACAGGUGACACCACCCGUCUUCCUGUCACAGACACUUCCUCAGCAUCCACAGGUCAGGCCACCCCUCUUCCUGUCACCAGCCUUUCCUCAGUAUCCACAGGUGACACCACCCCUCUUCUUGUCACCAACACUUCCUCAGUAUCCAGAGGUCACGCCACCUCUCUUCCUGUCACCAUCCCUUCCUCAUCAUCCUCAGGUCACACCACCCCUCUUCCUGUCACCAGCACUUCCUCAGUAUCUACAGGUCACGUCACCCCUCUUCCUGUCACCAGCACUUCCUCAGCAUCCACAGGUCACGCCACCUCUCUUCCUGUCACCGACACUUCCUCAGUAUCCACAGGUCACGCCACCUCUCUUCCUGUCACCGACACUUCCUCAGUAUCCACAGGUCACGCCACCCCUCUUCCUGUCACCGACGCUUCCUCAGUGUCCACAGGUCACGCCACGCCUCUUCCUGUCACCGACGCUUCCUCAGCAUCCACAGGUGACACCACCCCUCUUCCUGUCACCAACACUUCCUCAGCAUCCACAGGUCAGGCCACCCCUCUUCCUGUCACCAGCCUUUCCUCAGUAUCCACAGGUGACACCAUGCCUCUUCCUGUCACUAGCCCUUCCUCAGCAUCCACAGGUCACGCCACCCCUCUUCCUGUUACCGGCCUUUCCUCAGCUUCCACAGGUGACACCACCCCUCUUCCUGUCACUGACACUUCCUCAGCAUCCACAGGUCACGUCACCCCUCUUCCUGUCACCAGCCUUUCCUCAGCAUCCACAGGUGACAGCACCCCUCUUCCUGUCACUGACACUUCCUCAGCAUCCACAGGUCACGUCACCCCUCUUCCUGUCACCAGCCUUUCCUCAGCAUCCACAGGUGACACCACCCCUCUUCCUGUCACUGACACUUCCUCAGCAUCCACAGGUCACGCCACCCCUCUUCAUGUCACUGAUGCUUCCUCAGCAUCCACAGGUCAGGCCACCCUUCUUCCUGUCACCAGCCUUUCCUCAGUAUCCACAGGUGACACCACGCCUCUUCCUGUCACUAGCCCUUCCUCAGCAUCCACAGGUCACGCCACCCCUCUUCUUGUCACCGACACUUCCUCAGCAUCCACAGGACACGCCACCCCUCUUCCUGUCACGGACGCUUCCUCAGUGUCCACAGGUCACGCCACCUCUCUUCCUGUAACCAUCCGUUCCUCAGGUUCCACAGGUCACACCACCCCUCUUCCUGUCACCGACACUUCCUCAGCAUCCACAGGUCAGGCCACCUCUCUUCUUGUCACCGACACUUCCUCAGUAUCCACAGGUGACACCACGCCUCUUCCUGUCACUAGCACUUCCUCAGCAUCCACAGGUCACGUCACUCCUCUUCAUGUCACCAGCCCUUCCUCAGCAUCCACAGGUCACGCCACCCCUCUUCCUGUCACCAGCCUUUCCUCAGCAUCCACAGGUGACACCAUGCCUCUUCCUGUCACUAGCCCUUCCUCAGCAUCCACAGGUGACACCACCCCUCUUCCUGUCACCGACGCUUCCUCAGUAUCCACAGGUCACACCACCCCUCUUCCUGUCACCAGCCCUUCCUCAGCAUCUACAGGUCACACCACCCCUCUUCCUGUCACCGACACUACCUCAGCAUCCAAAGGUGACACCACCCCUCUUCCUGUCACCAGCCCUUCCUCAGCAUCUACAGGUCACACCACCCCUCUUCCUGUCACCGACACUUCCUCAGCAUCCACAGGUGACACCACCCCUCUUCCUGUCACCAGCCCUUCCUCAGCAUCCACAGGUCACGCCACCCCUCUUCCUGUCACCAAUGCUUCCUCAUUAUCCACAGGUCACGCCACCCCUCUUCAUGUCACCAGCCCUUCCUCAGCAUCCACAGGUCACGCCACCCCUCUUCCUGUCACCAGCACUUCCUCAGCAUCCACCGGUCACGCCACCUCUCUUCCUGUCACCAGCACUUCCUCAGCAUCCACCGGUCACGCCACCCCUCUUCCUGUCACCGACAAUUCCUCAGUAUCCACAGGUCACGCCACCCCUCUUCCUGUCACCGGCCUUUCCUCAGCUACCACAGAUGACACCACCCGUCUUCCUGUCACCGACGUUUCCUCGGCAUCCACAGGUCAGGCCACCCCUCUUCCUGUCACCAGCCUUUCCUCAGUAUCCACAGGUGACACCACGCCUCUUCCUGUCACUAGCCCUUCCUCAGCAUCCACAGGUCACGCCAGCCCUCUUCUUGUCACUGACGCUUCCUCAGCAUCCACAGGUCAGGCCACCCCUCUUCCUGUCACCGACACUUCCUCAGUAUCCACAGCUCACGCCACCCCACUUCCUGUCACCGGCCUUUCUUCAGCUUCCACAGAUGACACCACCCGUCUUCCUGUCACCGACGUUUCCUCGGCAUCCACAGGUCAGGCCAUCCCUCUUCCUGUCACCAGCCCUUCCUCAGCAUCCACAGGUGACACCACCCCUCUUCCUGUCACCGACGCUUCCUCAGCAUCCACAGGUGACACCACCUCUCUUCCUGUCACCAUCCCUUCCUCAGCAUCUUCAGGUCACACCACCUCUCUUCCUGUCACCGACGCUUCCUCAGUGUCCACAGGUCACGCCACCUCUCUUCUUGUCACCGACGCUUCCUCAGUAUCCACAGGUGACACCACCCCUCUUCCUGUCACCGACACUAACUCAGCAUCCACAGGUGACACCACCCCUCUUCAUGUCACCGACGCUUCCUCAGUAUCCACAGGUCACGCCACCUCUCUUCCUGUCACCAGCCUUUCCUCAGCAUCCACAGGUGACACCACGCCUCUUCCUGUCACUAGCCCUUCCUCAGCAUCCUCAGGUGACACCACCCCUCUUCCUGUCACCGACACUUCCUCAGCAUCCACAGGUCACGCCACCCAUCUUCCUGUCACCGGCCUUUCCUCAGCUUCCACAGGUGACACCACCCGUCUUCCUGUCACCAACGUUUCCUCGGCAUCCACAGGUCAUGCCACCCCUCUUCCUGUCACCAGCACUUCCUCAGCAUCCACAGGUGACACCACCCCUCUUCCUGGCACCGACACUUCCUCAGUAUCCACAGGUCACACCACCCCUCUUCUUGUCACCGACGCUUCGUCAGUAUCCACAGGUGACACCACCCGUCUUCCUGUCACCAGCCCUUCCUCAGCAUCUACAGGUCACACCACCCCUCUUCAUGUCACCGAUGCUUCCUCAGUAUCCACAGGUCACACCACCCCUCUUCCUGUCACCGACACUUCCUCAGCAUCCACAGGUCAGGCCACCUCUCUUCUUGUCACCGACACUUCCUCAGUAUCCACAGGUGACACCACGCCUCUUCCUGUCACUAGCACUUCCUCAGCAUCCACAGGUCACGUCACUCCUCUUCAUGUCACCAGCCCUUCCUCAGCAUCCACAGGUCACGCCACCCCUCUUCCUGUCACCAGCCUUUCCUCAGCAUCCACAGGUGACACCACCCCUCUUCCUGUCACCGACACUUCCUCAGUAUCCACAGGUCACACCACCCCUCUUCCUGUCACCAGCCCUUCCUCAGCAUCUACAGGUCACACCACCCCUCUUCCUGUCACCGACACUUCCUCAGCAUCCAAAGGUGACACCACCCCUCUUCCUGUCACCAGCCCUUCCUCAGCAUCUACAGGUCACACCACCCCUCUUCCUGUCACCGACACUUCCUCAGCAUCCACAGGUGACACCACCCCUCUUCCUGUCACCAAUGCUUCCUCAUUAUCCACAGGUCACGCCACCCCUCUUCAUGUCACCAGCCCUUCCUCAGCAUCCACAGGUCACGCCACCCCUCUUCCUGUCACCAGCACUUCCUCAGCAUCCACCGGUCACGCCACCCCUCUUCCUGUCACCAGCACUUCCUCAGCAUCCACCGGUCACGCCACCCCUCUUCCUGUCACCGACAAUUCCUCAGUAUCCACAGGUCAUGCCACCCCUCUUCCUGUCACCGGCCUUUCCUCAGCUACCACAGAUGACACCACCCGUCUUCCUGUCACCGACGUGUCCUCGGCAUCCACAGGUCAGGCCACCCCUCUUCCUGUCACCAGCCUUUCCUCAGUAUCCACAGGUGACACCACGCCUCUUCCUGUCACUAGCCCUUCCUCAGCAUCCACAGGUCACGCCAGCCCUCUUCUUGUCACUGACGCUUCCUCAGCAUCCACAGGUCAGGCCACCCCUCUUCCUGUCACCGACACUUCCUCAGUAUCCACAGCUCACGCCACCCCACUUCCUGUCACCGGCCUUUCCUCAGCUUCCACAGAUGACACCACCCGUCUUCCUGUCACCGACGUUUCCUCGGCAUCCACAGGUCAGGCCAUCCCUCUUCCUGUCACCAGCCCUUCCUCAGCAUCCACAGGUGACACCACCCCUCUUCCUGUCACCGACGCUUCCUCAGCAUCCACAGGUGACACCACCUCUCUUCCUGUCACCAUCCCUUCCUCAGCAUCUUCAGGUCACACCACCUCUCUUCCUGUCACCGACGCUUCCUCAGUGUCCACAGGUCACGCCACCUCUCUUCUUGUCACCGACGCUUCCUCAGUAUCCACAGGUGACACCACCCCUCUUCCUGUCACCGACACUAACUCAGCAUCCACAGGUGACACCACCCCUCUUCAUGUCACCGACGCUUCCUCAGUAUCCACAGGUCACGCCACCUCUCUUCCUGUCACCAGCCUUUCCUCAGCAUCCACAGGUGACACCACGCCUCUUCCUGUCACUAGCCCUUCCUCAGCAUCCUCAGGUCACACCACCUCUCUUCCUGUCACCGACGCUUCCUCAGUGUCCACAGGUCACGCCACCUCUCUUCCUGUCACCAUCCCUUCCUCAGCAUCCUCAGGUCACACCACCCCUCUUCCUGUCACCGACGCUUCCUCAGUACCCACAGGUCACGCCACCUCUCUUCCUGUCACCGACGCUUCCUCAGUGUCCACAGGUCACGCCACCCCUCUUCCUGUCACCGACGCUUCCUCAGUGUCCACAGGUCAUGCCACCCCUCUUCCGGUCACCGACACUUCCUCAGUAUCUACAGGACAGGCCACCCCUCUUCCUGUCACCAGCCUUUCCUCAGCAUCAUCCACUGGUGACACCACGCCGCUUCCUGUCACUGAUACUUCCUCAGCAUCCACAGGUCAGGACACCCCUCUUCCUGUCACCAGCCUUUUCUCAGUAUCCACAGGUGACACCACGCCUCUUCCUGUCACUAGCCCUUCCUCAGCAUCCACAGGUCACGCCACCCAUCUUCUUGUCACCGACGCUUCCUCAGUAUCCACAGGUCACGCCACCUCUCUUCUUGUCACCGACGCUUCCUCAGUAUCCACAGGUCACGCCACCGCUCUUCAUGUCACCGAUGCUUCCUCAUUAUCCACAGGGGACACCACCCCUCUUCCUGUCACCAGCCCUUCCUCAGCAUCCACAGGUGACACCACCCCUCUUCCUGUCACCGACACUUCCUCAGUAUCCACAGGUCACGCCACCUCUCUUCCUGUCACUGACACUUCCUCAGCAUCCACAGGUCACGCCACCUCUCUUCCUGUCACCGACACUUCCUCAGCAUCCACAGGUCAGGCCACCCCUCUUCCUGUCACCAGCCCUUCCUCAGCAUCCACAGGUCACGCCAUCCCUCUUCUUGUCACCGACACUUCCUCAGCAUCCACAGGACAGGCCACCCCUCUUCCUGUCACCAGCCUUUCCUCAGCAUCCACAGGUGACACCACCCCUCUUCCUGUCACCGAUGCUUCCUCAGUGUCCACAGGUCACGCCACCUCUCUUCCUGUCACCAGCCUUUCCUCAGUAUCCACAGGUGACACCACCCCUCUUCCUGUCACUAGCCCUUCCUCAGCAUCCACAGGUCACGCCACCCCUCUUCAUGUCACCAGCCCUUCCUCAGCAUCCACAGGUCACGCCACCCCUCUUCCUGUCACCAGCCUUUCCUCAGCAUCCACAGGUGACACCACGCCUCUUCCUGUCACUAGCCCUUCCUCAGCAUCCACAGGUCACGCCACCCCUCUUCAUGUCACCGACGCUUCCUCAGUAUCCACAGGUGACACCACCCCUCUUCCUGUCACCAGCCCUUCCUCAGCAUCCUCAGGUCACACCACCCCUCUUCCUGUCACCGACGCUUCCUCAGCAUCCACAGGUGACACCACCCCUCUUCCUGUCACCGACACUUCCUCAGCAUCCACAGGUCACGCCACCCAUCUUCCUGUCACCGGCCUUUCCUCAGCUUCCACAGGUGACACCACCCGUCUUCCUGUCACCGACGUUUCCUCGGCAUCCACAGGUCAUGCCACCCCUCUUCCUGUCACCAGCACUUCCUCAGCAUCCACAGGUGACACCACCCCUCUUCCUGGCACCGACACUUCCUCAGUAUCCACAGGUCACACCACCCCUCUUCUUGUCACCGACGCUUCGUCAGUAUCCACAGGUGACACCACCCGUCUUCCUGUCACCAGCCCUUCCUCAGCAUCUACAGGUCACACCACCCCUCUACCUGUCACCGACACUCCCUCAGCAUCCACAGGUGACACCACCCCUCUUCCUGUCACCAAUGCUUCCUCAUUAUCCACACGUCACGCCACCUCUCUUCAUGUCACCAGCCCUUCCUCAGCAUCCACCGGUCACGCCACCCCUCUUCCUGUUACCGACACUUCCGCAGCAUCCACAGGUCACGCCACCCCUCUUCCUGUCACCAGCACUUCCUCAGCAUCCACAGGUGACACCACCCCUCUUCCUGUCACCGACACUUCCUCAGCAUCCACAGGUCACGCCACCCCUCUUCCUGUCACCAACACUUCCUCAGUAUCCACAGGUCACGCCACCCCUCUUCAUGUCACCAGCCCUUCCUCAGCAUCCACAGGUCACACCACCCCUCUUCCUGUCACCGACGCUUCGUCAGUGUCCACAGGUCACGCCACCUCUCUUCCUGUCACCGACGCUUCCUCAGUGUCCACAGGUCACGCCACCCCUCUUCCUGUCACCGACGCUUCCUCAGUGUCCACAGGUCACGCUACCCCUCUUCCUCUCACCAGCCUUUCCUCAGUAUCCACAGGUGACACCACGCCUCUUCCUGUCACCGACACUUCCUCAGCAUCCACAGGUCAGGCCACCCCUCUUCCUGUCACCAGCCUUUCCUCAGUAUCCACAGGUGACACCACCCCUCUUCCUGUCACCGACACUUCCUCAGCAUCCACAGGUCACGCCACCUCUCUUCCUGUCACCGACACUUCCUCAGCAUCCACAGGUCACGCCACCCCUCUUCCUGUCACCGACACUUCCUCAAUAUCCACAGGUCACGCCACCCCUCUUCAUGUCACCAGCCCUUCCUCAGCAUCCACCGGUCACGCCACCCCGCUUCCUGUCACCGACACUUCCUCAGCAUCCACAGGUCACGCCACCCCUCUUCCUGUCACCAGCCUUUCCUCAGUAUCCACAGGUGACACCACGCCUCUUCCUGUCACUAGCCCUUCCUCAGCAUCCACAGGUCACGCCACUCCUCUUCUUGUCACCGACGCUUCCUCAGCAUCCACAGGUCAGGCCACCCCUCUUCCUGUCACCAGCCUUUCCUCAGUAUCCACAGGUGACACCACGCCUCUUCCUGUCACUAGCCCUUCCUCAGCAUCCACCGGUCAUGCCACCUCUCUUCCUGUCACCGACACUUCCUCAGCAUCCACAGGUGACACCACCUCUCUUCCUGUCACCGACACUUCCUCAGCAUACACAGGUGACACCACCUCUCUUCCUGUCACCGACACUUCCUCAUCAUCCACAGGUGACACCACCCCUCUUCUUGUCACCGAGACUUCCUCAGCAUCCACAGGUGACACCACCCCUGUGCCUGUCACCGACACUUCCUCAGUAUCCACAGGUCACGCCACCCCUCUUCCUGUCACCGGCCUUUCCUCAGCUUCCACAGGUGACACCACCCGUCUUCCUGUCACCGACAUUUCCUCGGCAUCCACAGGUCAGGCCACCCCUCUUCCUGUCACCAACACUUCCUCAGUAUCCACAGGUGACACCAUGCCUCUUCCUGUCACUAGCCCUUCCUCAGCAUCCACAGGUCACGCCACCCCUCUUCCUGUCACCAGCACUUCCUCAGCAUCCACCGGUCACGCCACCCCUGUUCCUGUCACCAGCACUUCCUUAGCAUCCACAGGUCACACCACCCCUCUUCCUGUCACCAGCCCUUCCUCAGCAUCUACAGGUCACACCACCCCUCUUCCUGUCACCGACACUUCCUCAGCAUCCACAGGUGACACCACCCCUCUUCCUGUCACCAAUGCUUCCUCAUUAUCCACAGGACACACCACCCCUCUUCAUGUCACCAUCCCUUCCUCAGCAUCCACAGGUGACACCAGCACUCUUCCUGUCACCGGCGCUUCCUCAGCAUCCACCGGUCACGCCACCCCUCUUCCUGUCACCGACACUUCCUCAGUAUCCACAGGUCACGCCACCCCUCUUCCUGUCACCAGCUUUUCCUCAGUAUCCACAGGUGACACCACCCCUCUUCCUGUCACCGACGCUUCCUCGGCAUCCACCGGUCACGCCACCCCUCUUCCUGUCACCGACACUUCCUCAGCAUCCACAGGUGACACCACCCCUCUUCCUGUCACCGACGCUUCCUCGGCAUCCACAGGUCAGGCCACCCCUCUUCCUGUCACCAGCCUUUCCUCAGUAUCAACAGGUGACACCACGCCUCUUCCUGUCACCAUCCCUUCCUCAGCAUCCUCAGGUCACACCACCUCUCUUCCUGUCAGCGACACUUCCUCAGCAUCCACAGGUCAGGCCACCCCUCUUCCUGUCACCAGCCUUUCCUCAGUAUCCACAGGUGACACCACCCCUCUUCUUGUCACCGACGCUUCCUCAGUAUCCACAGGUCACGCCACCCCUCUUCCUGUCACCGACACUUCCUCAGCAUCCACAGGUGACACCACCCGUCUUCCUGUCACGGACACUUCCUCAGCAUCCACAGGUCAGGCCACCCCUCUUCCUGUCACCAGCCUUUCCUCAGUAUCCACAGGUGACACCACCCCUCUUCUUGUCACCAACACUUCCUCAGUAUCCACAGGUCACGCCACCUCUCUUCCUGUCACCAUCCCUUCCUCAUCAUCCUCAGGUCACACCACCCCUCUUCCUGUCACCAGCACUUCCUCAGUAUCUACAGGUCACGUCACCCCUCUUCAUGUCACCAGCCCUUCCUCAUCAUCCACAGGUCAGGCCACCCCUCUUCCUGUCACCAGCACUUCCUCAGUAUCUACAGGUCACGUCACCCCUCUUCAUGUCACCAGCCCUUCCUCAGCAUCCACAGGUCACGCCACCCCUCUUCCUGUCACCAGCACUUCCUCAGCAUCCACAGGUCACGCCACCCCUCUUCCUGUCACCGACGCUUCCUCAGUGUCCACAGGUCACGCCACGCCUCUUCCUGUCACCGACACUUCCUCAGCAUCCACAGGUGACACCACCCCUCUUCCUGUCACCGACACUUCCUCAGCAUCCACAGGUCAGGCCACCCCUCUUCCUGUCACCAGCCUUUCCUCAGUAUCCACAGGUCACGCCACCCCUCUUGCUGUCAGCAGUGCUACCUCAGCUUCCACAGUAUCCUCGGACUCCCCUCUGAAGAUGGAAACAUCAGGAAUGACAACACCGUCACUGAAGACAGACGGUGGGAGACGCACAGCCACAUCACCACCCCCCACAACCUCCCAGACCAUCAUUUCCACCAUUCCCAGCACUGCCAUGCACACCCGCUCCACAGCUGCCCCCAUCCCCAUCCUGCCUGAGAGAGGAGUUUCCCUCUUCCCCUAUGGGGCAGACGCCGGGGACCUGGAGUUCGUCAGGAGGACCGUGGACUUCACCUCCCCACUCUUCAAGCCGGCGACUGGCUUCCCCCUUGGCUCCUCUCUCCGUGAUUCCCUCUACUUCACAGACAAUGGCCAGAUCAUCUUCCCAGAGUCAGACUACCAGAUUUUCUCCUACCCCAACCCACUCCCAACAGGCUUCACAGGCCGGGACCCUGUGGCCCUGGUGGCUCCGUUCUGGGACGAUGCUGACUUCUCCACUGGUCGGGGGACCACAUUUUAUCAGGAAUACGAGACGUUCUAUGGUGAACACAGCCUGCUAGUCCAGCAGGCCGAGUCUUGGAUUAGAAAGAUGACAAACAACGGGGGCUACAAGGCCAGGUGGGCCCUAAAGGUCACGUGGGUCAAUGCCCACGCCUAUCCUGCCCAGUGGACCCUCGGGAGCAACACCUACCAAGCCAUCCUCUCCACGGACGGGAGCAGGUCCUAUGCCCUGUUUCUCUACCAGAGCGGUGGGAUGCAGUGGGACGUGGCCCAGCGCUCAGGCAACCCGGUGCUCAUGGGCUUCUCUAGUGGAGAUGGCUAUUUCGAAAACAGCCCACUGAUGUCCCAGCCAGUGUGGGAGAGGUAUCGCCCUGAUAGAUUCCUGAAUUCCAACUCAGGCCUCCAAGGGCUGCAGUUCUACAGGCUACACCGGGAAGAAAGGCCCAACUACCGUCUCGAGUGCCUGCAGUGGCUGAAGAGCCAGCCUCGGUGGCCCAGCUGGGGCUGGAACCAGGUCUCCUGCCCUUGUUCCUGGCAGCAGGGACGACGGGACUUACGAUUCCAACCCGUCAGCAUAGGUCGCUGGGGCCUCGGCAGUAGGCAGCUGUGCAGCUUCACCUCUUGGCGAGGAGGCGUGUGCUGCAGCUACGGGCCCUGGGGAGAGUUUCGUGAAGGCUGGCACGUGCAGCGUCCUUGGCAGUUGGCCCAGGAACUGGAGCCACAGAGCUGGUGCUGCCGCUGGAAUGACAAGCCCUACCUCUGUGCCCUGUACCAGCAGAGGCGGCCCCACGUGGGCUGUGCUACAUACAGGCCCCCACAGCCCGCCUGGAUGUUCGGGGACCCCCACAUCACCACCUUGGAUGGUGUCAGUUACACCUUCAAUGGGCUGGGGGACUUCCUGCUGGUCGGGGCCCAAGACGGGAACUCCUCCUUCCUGCUUCAGGGCCGCACCGCCCAGACUGGCUCAGCCCAGGCCACCAACUUCAUCGCCUUUGCGGCUCAGUACCGCUCCAGCAGCCUGGGCCCCGUCACGGUCCAAUGGCUCCUUGAGCCUCACGACGCAAUCCGUGUCCUGCUGGAUAACCAGACUGUGACAUUUCAGCCUGACCAUGAAGACGGCGGAGGCCAGGAGACGUUCAACGCCACCGGAGUCCUCCUGAGCCGCAACGGCUCUGAGGUCUCGGCCAGCUUCGACGGCUGGGCCACCGUCUCGGUGAUCGCGCUCUCCAACAUCCUCCACGCCUCCGCCAGCCUCCCGCCCGAGUACCAGAACCGCACGGAGGGGCUCCUGGGGGUCUGGAAUAACAAUCCAGAGGACGACUUCAGGAUGCCCAAUGGCUCCACCAUUCCCCCAGGGAGCCCUGAGGAGAUGCUUUUCCACUUUGGAAUGACCUGGCAGAUCAACGGGACAGGCCUCCUUGGCAAGAGGAAUGACCAGCUGCCUUCCAACUUCACCCCUGUUUUCUACUCACAACUGCAAAAAAACAGCUCCUGGGCUGAACAUUUGAUCUCCAACUGUGACGGAGAUAGCUCAUGCAUCUAUGACACCCUGGCCCUGCGCAACGCAAGCAUCGGACUUCACACGAGGGAAGUCAGUAAAAACUACGAGCAGGCGAACGCCACCCUCAAUCAGUACCCGCCCUCCAUCAAUGGUGGUCGUGUGAUUGAAGCCUACAAGGGGCAGACCACGCUGAUUCAGUACACCAGCAAUGCUGAGGAUGCCAACUUCACGCUCAGAGACAGCUGCACCGACUUGGAGCUCUUUGAGAAUGGGACGUUGCUGUGGACACCCAAGUCGCUGGAGCCAUUCACUCUGGAGAUUCUAGCAAGAAGUGCCAAGAUUGGCUUGGCAUCUGCACUCCAGCCCAGGACUGUGGUCUGCCAUUGCAAUGCAGAGAGCCAGUGUUUGUACAAUCAGACCAGCAGGGUGGGCAACUCCUCCCUGGAGGUGGCUGGCUGCAAGUGUGACGGGGGCACCUUCGGCCGCUACUGCGAGGGCUCCGAGGAUGCCUGUGAGGAGCCGUGCUUCCCGAGUGUCCACUGCGUUCCUGGGAAGGGCUGCGAGGCCUGCCCUCCAAACCUGACUGGGGAUGGGCGGCACUGUGCGGCUCUGGGGAGCUCUUUCCUGUGUCAGAACCAGUCCUGCCCUGUGAAUUACUGCUACAAUCAAGGCCACUGCUACAUCUCCCAGACUCUGGGCUGUCAGCCCAUGUGCACCUGCCCCCCAGCCUUCACUGACAGCCGCUGCUUCCUGGCUGGGAACAACUUCAGUCCAACUGUCAACCUAGAACUUCCCUUAAGAGUCAUCCAGCUCUUGCUCAGUGAAGAGGAAAAUGCCUCCAUGGCAGAAGUCAACGCCUCGGUGGCAUACAGACUGGGGACCCUGGACAUGCGGGCCUUUCUCCGCAACAGCCAAGUGGAACGAAUCGAUUCUGCAGCACCGGCCUCGGGAAGCCCCAUCCAACACUGGAUGGUCAUCUCGGAGUUCCAGUACCGCCCUCGGGGCCCGGUCAUUGACUUCCUGAACAACCAGCUGCUGGCCGCGGUGGUGGAGGCGUUCUUAUACCACGUUCCACGGAGGAGUGAGGAGCCCAGGAACGACGUGGUCUUCCAGCCCAUCUCCGGGGAAGACGUGCGCGAUGUGACAGCCCUGAACGUGAGCACGCUGAAGGCUUACUUCAGAUGCGAUGGCUACAAGGGCUACGACCUGGUCUACAGCCCCCAGAGCGGCUUCACCUGCGUGUCCCCGUGCAGUAGGGGCUACUGUGACCAUGGAGGCCAGUGCCAGCACCUGCCCAGUGGGCCCCGCUGCAGCUGUGUGUCCUUCUCCAUCUACACGGCCUGGGGCGAGCACUGUGAGCACCUGAGCAUGAAACUCGACGCGUUCUUCGGCAUCUUCUUUGGGGCCCUGGGCGGCCUCUUGCUGCUGGGGGUCGGGACGUUCGUGGUCCUGCGCUUCUGGGGUUGCUCCGGGGCCAGGUUCUCCUAUUUCCUGAACUCAGCUGAGGCCUUGCCUUGAAGGGGCAGCUGUGGCCUAGGCUACCUCAAGACUCACCUCAUCCUUACCGCACAUUUAAGGCGCCAUUGCUUUUGGGAGACUGGAAAAGGGAAGGUGACUGAAGGCUGUCAGGAUUCUUCAAGGAGAAUGAAUACUGGGAAUCAAGACAAGACUAUACCUUAUCCAUAGGCGCAGGUGCACAGGGGGAGGCCAUAAAGAUCAAACAUGCAUGGAUGGGUCCUCACGCAGACACACCCACAGAAGGACACUAGCCUGUGCACGCGCGCGUGCACACACACACACACACACACGAGUUCAUAAUGUGGUGAUGGCCCUAAGUUAAGCAAAAUGCUUCUGCACACAAAACUCUCUGGUUUACUUCAAAUUAACUCUAUUUAAAUAAAGUCUCUCUGACUUUUUGUGUCUCCAAAA